GUAGUCUGUUGGGAGUUGAGGGAGGGGGACAACGCGGCGUGUGAAGAGUGGGGAAGAAAUCACGCGACUGGAUUUGGAGUUCUGCUGGGCUCGAAUCUCAGCUGUGCUUUUUAUUAACCGUGGGACCUUGAGCUACUCGGCUCUCCUUUCUGAAUGACAGUUUCCUCCUCUGUAAAACAGGAAUGGUUAAUUCAACGAAUGUUUACUGAGCGCUUAGUCCAGUGGUGCAGGUUUAAGGCUGGAGGCAGCGGAAAAGGAAAACAAGGUUCCUGGUCUCGGGAAGCUUACCAUGGGGGUGUCUGUACGCGUGUGUGUUCGUGCGCUCAGUGGUGGAAGACAGGACAGAAAAUAAACGGAUCAACAUCCAAAGCAACAAGGUCAUUACAGCUUAUGGGGAAACUGACUCGAUGAAGCUCAGGCCUGGCCGCGGUCAGGGUAGAAUCAGGACUAGAACCCAGGCUGUGUGGCUGCAGCCCUGACCCUCACCAUCCAGGUCAGGCAGAGAACACUCAGGUGGGGCAGGAGGUCUUGGCCCCCAUGGUGUGGGGCUUGGUCACAGCUGCUUCCCCAGCCCCAGGCCUGCACGAAGAAGGCACUCACUAAAUGCUUGCUGUUGAGGUGAGUGAAGCUGAGGGUGGAAUCCGAGAGUGGGAGGAGGAGGAGAAGGAGGAGGAGGCAGCAGAGAGGACGCCCACAGGAGAAAAGUCUCCAAACUCUCCCAGGACUUUGCUGUCUCUGAGAGGGAAGGCCCGGACGGGGGGCCCCAUGGAAGUCAAGCUGGAGCUGCACCCCUUGCAGAACAGGUGGGCUCUGUGGUUCUUCAAGAAUGACCGCAGCCGGGCCUGGCAGGACAACCUGCACCUGGUCACCAAGGUGGACACUGUGGAGGACUUCUGGGCGCUAUACAGUCACAUCCAGCUGGCCAGCAAGCUCUCCUCUGGCUGUGACUACGCCCUCUUCAAGGAUGGCAUCCAGCCCAUGUGGGAGGACAGCAGGAAUAAACGGGGUGGCCGCUGGCUGGUCAGCCUGGCCAAGCAGCAGCGCCACAUUGAGCUGGACCGGCUGUGGCUGGAGACGCUGCUGUGUCUGAUCGGGGAGAGCUUUGAGGAACACAGCAGAGAGGUAUGUGGGGCCGUCGUCAACAUCCGCACCAAGGGGGACAAGAUCGCUGUGUGGACGAGGGAGGCGGAAAACCAGGCGGGCGUGCUGCACGUUGGGCGUGUAUACAAAGAGCGCCUGGGCCUCUCCCCAAAGACCAUCAUUGGGUACCAGGCCCAUGCAGACACAGCCACCAAGAGCAACUCCCUAGCCAAGAACAAGUUUGUGGUGUGAGGGGGGCCUUGGCACCCCUCCUAUGUAAUGGGACAGCCGCCACUGAGCCUCAUUACUUUGGGGGAUGGGGCGGGACUGGGGAUCAGACAGCCUAGUUCUUACCUGUCCUCAAGUGAACAGGAAUGCAAACACUCUUUAACAUGAGUUGGGGCCUGAGCCUUAGGGGCUAGAUGGGGGUAGUGGUGGCAGUCUGAGGACCUAGCUUGUCCUGGGGCCACAGGACAGCAGCAGGGUGGAAAAAACUCCUGAGGGUGGGGUGAGUCAUGGCGGGGAAGGAGGGCUCUAUGGUAGGCGGAGAAACCCAUAGUCCAGCGUUUACUGUUUCCACCCAGGAAGGAGGUGAGGUGGCCUGAGAGACAGACUCUUCCAUGGGUGGUGGGCUCAAGGGCACAGACAUUCUGGAGGGUGAACGCCAUCAUUUGUACAGAGGGAUACGUGGGUUGCUGAGGACUGAGAGAGCCUUGCAAGGCCGCUCCCCUUCUCCCCAGCUGUGACCAGGGCUGUCUGGGCCUUGCCUGCCUCAGGGCCAGACUGAAGUGGAGGUGGAGGGAUGCUGGGCUAGGCCUCACCAAGGUUCUGGUAGAAGUGGUGGAAGUGGAUAAACUUGAUAAUAAAAGCUUAAGCAUCUUUCUGUUCCUGUUUUAAAUAAAUACUUCUGAACAAA